AGUAGGCAGCAGCGGCGGCGGCGGAGGAGGAGGCGGUGGUGGAGGUGCGCGGCCUGAAGAGGAGGAUGGAGGAGCAGCAGAAGGAGGGCGAGGCCGAGGUCGCGGAGCACUGGUUUUCCAAGUGGGAGCGCCAGUGCCUGGCUGAGGCCGAGCAGGAGGAGCAGCUGCCCCCCGAGCUGCAGGAGGAGGCGGCUGCAGAGUUGGCAGGGCUCAAGAGCGAGAAGCAGAAGCUGUGGCACCUCUUCCAGAUCUCGGCCACCGCCGUUGCUCAGCUUUACAAGGAUUCUGGGUGCCAACAGCAAGGACUUUCCAUGUGGGACCCCUUCCAGAAUGCGGCCAUGGCCGUGACCAGCCUCUACAAAGAGAGCGGGGAUGCCCACCAACGAAGUUUUGACUUGGGUGUCCAGGUUGGCCACCAGCGUCGCAUCAAAGAUGUGCUGGAGUGGGUGAAAAAGGGCCGGAGCACCAUUCGUCGCGAAGACUUGAUUAGCUUCCUGUGUGGCAAAGUGCCCCCCGCUCCUCCUCCACCUCGCACUCCUAGGACACCCCCGAAGCCACCCACUGGGGUCACCAGCCAGGCUGUGGCAACUGAGUCCAGCUCAUCGGUGGACGUCGACCUGCAGCCCUUCCAGGAGGCGAUCGCCCUGCAUGGCCUCAGUGGUGCUAUGGCCGGCAUCAGCAUGCGAUCGGGCGACUCGCCUCAAGACAGCGGUGUCGCCAGCAGUGGGCGCCGAAAAACUAGCUUCUUGGAGGACGACUUGAAUCCCUUCGACUCAGAGGAACUGGCCCUCCACCUGGACAGUGGGGGGAUCCGCAAGCGCACCUCGGCCCAAUGCAGUGAUGGCAUCACAGACUCCCCAAUCCAAAAGCGCAACCGAAUGGUCUAAACUGCCUCAUUGGUUGCCUGCCGCCAUAUUGCUUGAGAGUGAACUCAACCGUCGACAUGCUUGUCUAAAGGUUACUGGAGACCAUUUUUCUUCCCUUCUCUAAGUUAAACAAAGAUUUCUAACAAUUUUGCCAUAAAGAAACUUUAAAAGUAUUCCAGAAGAGGCUUCAUAUGACUCUGACUUUCCAAAAAAUAUAAUCCUAGCAGAGAACAAAUAUGUAGUAGUUAGCAGGAUCAUUUAAAGCAAACGUAUCUGGUCAAGGCAGGAGUCUGAUUUAUCUUGUUCACAGUUAUAUUCCUCAGCACCUAGCACAGUUCCAGGUGCUCAAUAAAUGUUCAUUGAAUGAA